AGAGCGCGCCGCGGAGCCGGGGCGCCCUCACUGCGCUAGGAGCCCCACUAAACCCAGCGGAGCGGAGCCUGGCGGGAGGCAGCGCCGCGGAGCCAGCGCCGGACGCCGCAAGCAGACUCCCCGGCCAGCGCAAGCACUCCCUGGCCGGCGCCGGACCCUCGGGGCGCCGGAUUCGUCUUGUGUGCCCCACGUCAUGCGCGCGGGCGUCCGCGGCUCUCCCGACCAGCCCCAGCGCGGUGGGCCCAGGCUCAGAGGUCCCGGCGCCUCUCGCUGAAGUAGUUGGGUAGCCGGGGCUGGGGGUCGCCACGUCGGGGGCGCGGCCAGGACCCGCGGAGCCGGUCCCCGAGCGCGGGGAGCGGGGCCGCCCGCGCCGCCCCACCAUUACCUCCCCGGGCGGCAAGGAGGAGCUGGUGGCGGUCGCCUCCCGGCUGUGGCAGCGGCGGCGGCGUGCCUGCCUGGCGGCCGUCGGCGUACUCUUGGCCAUGGCGCUCGGGCUGCUCAUCGCCGUGCCGCUGCUGCUGCAGGCGGCGCCCCGAGGCGCCGCGCACUAUGAGAUGAUGGGCACCUGCCGCAUGAUCUGCGACCCUUACACUGCCGCGCCCGGCGGGGAGCCCCCGGGUGCAAAGGCGCAGCCACCCGGACCCAGCACCGCCGCCCUGGAAGUCAUGCAGGACCUCAGCGCCAACCCUCCUCCUCCUUUCAUCCAGGGACCCAAGGGCGACCCGGGGCGACCGGGCAAGCCAGGGCCGCGGGGGCCCCCUGGAGAGCCGGGCCCGCCUGGACCCAGGGGCCCUCCGGGAGAGAAGGGCGACUCGGGGCGGCCCGGGCUGCCAGGGCUGCAACUGACGGCGGGCACGGCCAGCGGCGUCGGGGUGGUGGGCGGCGGGGCCGGGGUAGGUGGCGAUUCCGAGGGUGAAGUGACCAGUGCGCUGAGCGCCACCUUCAGCGGCCCCAAGAUCGCCUUCUAUGUGGGUCUCAAGAGCCCCCACGAAGGCUAUGAGGUGCUGAAGUUCGAUGACGUGGUCACCAACCUCGGCAAUCACUAUGACCCCACCACGGGCAAGUUCAGCUGCCAGGUACGCGGCAUCUACUUCUUCACCUACCACAUCCUCAUGCGCGGCGGCGACGGCACCAGCAUGUGGGCGGACCUCUGCAAGAACGGGCAGGUCCGGGCCAGCGCCAUUGCACAGGACGCCGACCAGAACUACGACUACGCCAGUAACAGCGUGGUGCUGCACUUGGAUUCAGGGGACGAAGUGUAUGUGAAGCUGGAUGGCGGGAAGGCUCACGGAGGCAAUAAUAACAAGUACAGCACGUUCUCGGGCUUUCUUCUGUACCCGGAUUAGGGGCGCGGGGGGUGCGAGGCGGGGUGGCUGCAGGCCGCCCGGUCUCCGCCCGGGCGCGGCUCCUUGGCAAAGGCCACUCUCGAUUCAUAACACUUCCUGACAUCUCCUUUGGAAAAGACAAAUCCCUGCGUCCUCCCUGCCCCGCUCCUGGCCUCAGUGCGUCUGCGACCCACCACGCUCAGGGCUGUGCUCCUGGUCUCCAUCCCCAUCCCGGCAAGGGAGGAAGGGACGCCCGAGCCCUUGAGGCGGCGGCACAGACUUUGCAAACCUGAUUAGACUGGACAGGCAGGGCCGGGAGCCUGCCCUCCUCAGACAGCCUCCUCCCAGUGCCUAGAAGCGGAGGGCUCCGGGCCCUGGCCAGGGAGGUAGGCCAGAGGGAGCGCGGGCUUCCUGGGGCGUCCUUCUUUGUGACCCGAAAUACUUGUGCAGAUUUCCCUGUCCAUCAGCCAAAACCCCACCCACAGCAGAAUUCCAGCAAACAGAAAAUUCACCUCUCCACACCGCAUUCCCUCCUGACUCAGACUCACCGCGAUGCAUUAAAUUAUGUUUUUAGACUAUG